CUCGUGCCAACGUGUCUUGUAAGGUGCGGCUAGAAACUGGGGACAUGGCAGCGCCUGGCCCAGCGCUCUGCCUCUUCGACGUGGAUGGGACCCUCACCGCCCCGCGGCAGAAAAUUACCAAAGAAAUGGAUGACUUCCUACAAAAAUUGAGGCAGAAGAUCAAAAUCGGAGUGGUAGGCGGAUCGGACUUUGAGAAAGUGCAGGAGCAACUGGGAAAUGAUGUGGUUGAAAAAUACGAUUAUGUGUUUCCAGAAAAUGGCUUGGUAGCAUACAAAGAUGGGAAACUCUUGUGUAGACAGAAUAUUCAAAGUCAUCUGGGUGAGGCCCUAAUCCAAGAUUUAAUCAACUACUGUCUGAGCUACAUUGCGAAAAUUAAACUCCCGAAGAAGAGGGGUACUUUCAUUGAAUUCCGAAAUGGGAUGUUAAACGUGUCCCCUAUUGGAAGAAGCUGCAGCCAAGAAGAACGCAUUGAGUUCUACGAACUCGAUAAAAAAGAAAAUAUAAGACAAAAGUUUGUAGCAGAUCUACGGAAAGAGUUUGCUGGAAAAGGCCUCACGUUUUCCAUAGGAGGCCAGAUCAGCUUUGAUGUCUUUCCUGAUGGAUGGGACAAGAGAUACUGUCUGCGACAUGUGGAAAAUGACGGUUAUAAGACCAUUUAUUUCUUUGGAGACAAAACUAUGCCAGGUGGCAAUGACCAUGAGAUCUUCACAGACCCCAGAACCAUGGGCUACUCCGUGACAGCGCCUGAGGACACGCGCAGGAUCUGUGAACUGCUGUUCUCCUAACGUGGGAGCGGGAGGGGCGGGGUCCCGGCUGACAAGCCAGCAUAGGGCAUUCGGUGGCCAGAGCCGAGGGUCCUCCCACACGUGCUCACCCACCCGCAGCCUAGGCAGGCUCUGCAUGCUAUGCCAGGCAUGUGCAGUCUGGACUUCCACCUCCAGUGCCAGAAACUUCCAGAAGGAAGGAGAAAACUCUUGUCAAGAAUGGCCCAGAGGAAUGCCUCGCACAAAAGGUCUUCCCCACCCACCCCCAGCCCCCUAGUCUAAUACCCACCCUGAUACGUGCAAUCAUGUAGUUUUGGCGGAAAUUUCCCCAUCAUUCUAGGAUGAUACAGAAAGAAAAACUGUGCCUGGACCCUCCCUCUUGGUGGGUCUGUGGAAACAUAAGCGGUUUUUUUAAUGGGCCCCUGCAUCAAUACCAAACAUGGGGGUUUGGUAAUGAGAAACCAGGACAGGCCAUCUGCAGUGACCCAGCCCAGGACGAAGUUUACAAACACCUCCUGGAACGAAGCUCCCGCCUGCAUGUCACCUUGAUGGGGGCUGUGAGUGGGGCAGUGUGAUACCCAGUGACUAGACGCACUCUGCGUUUUCCCGUGUUUGGGGCUGAGGCCUGCUGGACAGAUGGCUGGCCAAGUGGGAGCAGACCCUAGGGAGUUUGCACCUCGGCUGGGCCGGAUUCGGACCGGCUCUGUGUUCACUACACUCAGAAUAGCCUGGCUGCUUCUCUGUCUCCGAGACCGGAGGUAGUGGGAACCAACAGCUGGGCUGGAGAGUUGGUGCUGGCAAAACAGUCCUUGCCCUGGGGCCGGUUCUUACCCAGGUCCAGAGAAACCAACGCGGGAUGUCAGACUUCACCAAAAGGACUUUCUGGUUGCCCCUGGCUGGCUUCCUGGAGGCGUUCGCCUCUAGUUUCUCAGGGAUGGAGCGAGAGCCCAGCCAGAGAACAGUAAGAGGAGCUGCUCUCCUAUCUGCACUCACCCAGGCCUUCACCCAGACUUUACCACGGAGGCGGCUGAGUGCAGCUACAGCUAGGUCCGCGUCCCUCACUCUUUUCAUCUUCUGCACGUUCUUCGUGAAACUGGAAGGAUCCCGGGUCUCAGCUAGAACACGGUGGAAGAGAACUUUCCUAGGAAACGGUUCAUGUGUCACUUUUCAGGAUGUGGAAACACUGAGCCAUACACCCUCCAUUGCUUGGUGCUGGGGUUGUGUGGCCUCCACUGGGCACUUGCCGACCUGAGUCUGGGGCCAGGGGAGCCCAGGCUGCCCUGCACUCCUGCCUCCCAGCCCACAGCCAGGUGCUUUCAUCACAGCUAAACCUGGUUCCCUCCAAACCUCCCAGCCACUCGGGCUUGUAACUGUCUGAGCCCCGGAUCCGGUGGGGUGAAAGCAGCCAGCUCAUCCCAGUGACUCACAGGACACAGCCAUCCAGCGGCAUCUUUCCUUGUCGAAUGAUACUGUAAUGACCUUCCAAAGUGAAGAGUAGCACAUUAAAGUGAUUUUAUUGUU